UGGUUGUGUGACUGAUGGUCCUUGGGGAGCCCAGCAGUGAGGAUCUCAGCAGCCCACCUGUCUCAGAGUCCCCGCUGUGCACCCAGGCCCAGGGCUCAGUGAGUGAGAGCUCUCCGACCUCGGUGGGGGCGGGGCUAAUUGACCUUCAGACCCACCGUGUGCCAGUGCUGGCUGGCACACAGCACUGCUUGGACUUCCCCUGUGGGAAAGGAUGGGGACAGAUCAGUCUUUGGAAGAAUGGAGCGCUGGCUUUGCUCAGCCCUGUUCUUGGGAAGGUUUGAUCUGGAGAGCCGCAGCAGCCAGACCCUGGGGAGGCAGGUUAGUGAGCAGGCUCCCAACUUACGAGCUAGGAAGGCUGACGGCUGCUCAUUUCCCCCCAUGUGGACCUCAUCAGGGGGUCCUUCCUGAGGGCGAGCGCUAGGUUCGUCUGCGUUUCUCUCUCCCAGUUGGGCCUGACUCUGGACGCCAGGCUGAGGGAGUACACAGCUCCUUCAGAGCACGGGCUCAGACGCUCAGAUGCUCGGAGCGCUUCCGGCUGCUUUUCCAUGGGUAACUCACAUGUUCUUCCUGCAGGCUGGCAUUUGUCUUUCAUGGCUUUUUUCCAUCGGUCAGAAUUACAGUCUUUUGAUUGUAUGUACGUACCUGGUUAUUAUCAGAUAUCUAGUUUAAAAUGUGCAUCUGAAUAUAGAUUUUCUUGGUGAACGCAUUGCGUUCUCAUUCCGUAAAAAGUCGGAAGCUCAAAAUGAUGCUUAAAAAAAAAUCUUAGCAAGCUCUCCUGUGCAGAUGCUGCUGGCGCUGAGCUUUGUGCCUGGGGCAGAAAGGGUGAGGACGGCCCCGGUUGGUUUAGGAAAAGUGGUUAUGAACAGAACGGGCCCCAUGCUCCUGGCCUGAGGAAAUGUUGUGUGAAAAAGAUGGCUUCUACAGCUUGAAGGGGGACGGUCCACCUGAUGCUCCUGUCCCUCUCUGAGCCCCAGGGGCAGAAGGGAAACAGUCAAUAGCACGGCCGUUGCAGAUGGUGCCCAUAGAGGGAGGGUAGUUAGUGUCUGAGCAGGAGAGGGUGACCGGCCUUUGUGGGGCUGCUUCAGAGAGCCGGGCAGAGUCUGGGCCCCAACGUGGACUAGCAGGGGAGGAGCUCUCCUGGCUGGGGUGGCGACUCGGGGAGGUCUGGGUUGCCUGAGCAGGGAAUCGGCCUCCAGUGGGGGAGGUUCUGAGUGGGACGCGCUCUUCGUGUGGGCCUGGAGGACCUCUAGGCGGCCUGCACUCGCCUGAUACAGCUGGCUUCUGCUGGGAGGCUGGGUUUGCAUCCAAACUCUGAGACCUUUUGGACAAAACAUGCCAAAGAAGUUGGUGGUAGUAAGAAAUUCAUACUAAACUUGUUCUGUUAGGGUUUUUUUCCUUCCAGGUAUAUUAUUUCCCUUCAGUAGCCCUACAUUUUAAAAGUUAACGUUCAGCGUUGAGUCAGGGUCAGGUUUUGAAUGACACAGGAUGUUUUCAGAUCCUGAGUUUACCUGAAGCUCUCAAAGUAGCCUCCUAACAAAAAUUAUUGAAAACAUCAACUAUUUUGGAAUACUUUUAGGUAUGUAGAAAAAUUGCAGACGACACAGAAUUUCCAUAAUUUCCCCCAGCCAGCUUCCCCUAAUGCCAUGACAUGACCGUGAUACCUCUGUCACUCUGUCGAAACUGAGGUGUUCGCGCUGGCACCACACUACUCACCGAGCGACAGGCCUGUUUUGGAUUUUAUCAGUUUUCCUCCUGAUGUCCUUGCUGUCCCAGGACCCCGCCCCGGUGCCACAUCGCAUCGCGUUGUCCUGUCUCAUUCGCCCCCUCUGGUGUAGGAUAGCUGCCGUCCUUCCUUGUUUGUCAUCAGCUUGGUACUUUUGAGGAGUCCUGGUCAGGUAUUUUGCAGAAUGUGCCUUCAUUUGGGUUUGUUUGAUGUCUUGUGGUUGGACAGGUUGUGGGGUUAGGAAGAAUCCCACAGAGAUGAGGUGCCCUUAGUGCGUCGUAUUGGGGUACAGGACAUCCACGUGACUCAUCGCUGGUGACGUUCAACAAAAUUACUUACAAAACUUUUAAAAAAUUAUUAUUGUUUGCUUUAGAGAUGAGCUCUCGCUCUGUCAUCCAGGCUGGAGUGCAGUGGUGGGAUCAUAGCUCACUGCAGUCUCCAACUCCUGGGCUCAAGCGACCCCCCCACCUCAGCCUCCUGAGUAGCUGGGGCUACAGGUACGUGCCACUGUGUCUGGCAAAAUUAGUUUUACUUUACCAAAAGGAAGCACAUAGGCCUGCUCUGCUCUCUGCUACUUGGGGGUUUUGUGUCAUAGAUUGUAGGACACUGGUGGUAAUUUAAUUUCAGAAGGGACCUUCUUGCUCACCCAGUUGGAUCCUUCCAGUUUCUAGAUGAAGACACUUGGGACCUGGAGGCCUUCUGACUUUUGGGUCAGAGCUGGCAUGGAGUCCAGGCACCUGCUUUCUGCAGGCAUGCAUGCUCCUGGGACACUCUGCAGGGACAGAGCCAUCCCCAGCAAGGCAGACUGACAGGGCUGGUUUCCAGUCGGGUGGGGCCGCAUCCCUCCAGGGGAUGUGAGGCAGGUUUGAGAUGAGUCUGCUCCCCUUCUGCCUGCUGCUCCUGUCUUUUUUUUUCUUUUUCUUUUUCUUUUCUUUUUUUUUUUUUGAGACGGAGUCUCGCUCUGUUUCCAAGGCUGGAGUGCAGUGGCGCGAUCUCAGCUCACUGCAACCUCUGCCUCCCAGGUUCAAGUGGUACUCCUGCCUCAGCCUCCCAAGUAGCUGAGACUACAGGCAUGCGCCCCCACACCUGGCUUAUUUUGCGUUUUUAGUAGAGACAGGGUUUCUCCAUGUUGGUCAGGCUGGUCUCCAAUUCCUGACCUCAGGUGAUCCUCCCAAAGUGCUGGGAUCACAGGCGUGAGCCACCGCAACUGGCCUAGGAGUAACUUCUUAAUGAAUAUUUUAAUAAUAUAAAUCUUAGUCUGAAUUUCUGACUGUGUCGCCUAGAUGCCAUGUAGGGGAAUGGGCAGGUCAGAGGGUGUGGCCUGCGGUGUGGCGAGGCACUGAGGAUUAGGUGCUGCAGUUUUCCUCCGGCCCCUCCUGGUUCCCUGGUGAACACACAUCAGCCUCAGAUGGGCGACCCCCUACUCAUGGGAGGGCUGGGAGUGUGGGCCUUGUAGUUGGAUUCUGCUUCAGAAUUGCGUGUGACCUCACUGUGGAGUGUUUGACUGGACAAAAGCCUGCUGUAUACUCAGUGUCCCCAUCUGUAGAAAGGAUGCCGAUGGUACCCACCCCCAGAGUUGUUUUGAGGACUAACCACGAUAAUACAUGUAAAAUGCUCAGAAGAAUGUGUGGCAAACAGCAAGCACUUAAUAAAUUUUUUUUUUUAGUAGAGAAAAAUGGCAUUUUAUUUAUUUUAAACAACAGCAUUUAAAGUUAUACCUAUAAGGGGCACACAGAAGAUAUAUGGAGAGUUUAAAGAAUGAAAAUAAACUCACACGUGCCCACCACCCUACUUGAAAAACAGGAUUUUACCAGAAGGCUCGAGUGGCCCUCCAGAUUGUAGUUUCUGGCCCCUCCCGUUCAGAGGUAACUGGCAUCCUGGUUUUCAUGUUGAUCAGUGGUGUUUAAAGUACACCUGUAGGAAGUUCCAAAGUGCAGGAAGGGAACAAAGCCUCCUUGCAGAGAAAUCUUGUACUUUGGUGUUUCAUCAUCUGUUUGUGUGACAAAUAUACAACGUUAAUGUUGAAGAUGUGGGUUAGUGAAAUUGAGACCUGGCGCUUCCUGAGGCUGGCAGCCCGGUUGAGCCUGAGGACCAGACUUGAGGCAGUUGGCAGUCCGCGCCUCGUUGCCCUCUGUCUGCCCUGGGUAAGUGAGAGGCUCCUUGGGAGGCCAGUGGAGAUGGCUGUGGGAGGACAGAUUGAGUAGCUGUCCUUGGAGCUGCUCCUCCCUCCCUUCGUGGAGAAAUAGAAACAGCUUUCCUCCGGCCCUCACCUGUUGCCAGGGCUCCACGCUGGUGGGGGCGAGCUGCGUUUUGCUGAGUUGCACCGUGGGAGAGCGUUGGUGACCACUUGCCUGCUGUGGGCCAGCUCCCCGUGGCCAAGGACCAGCGUGGGCAGGGCCUUCGGGCACGGGUUGCUGGUACGAGCACACCGAGAAUCCCCUCCGCCAUAGGGCCUGCCCUGUGAGCUGCCCACCAGAUUCCACGGAGUGCUUCACACUCCUGUCUGGUGUGGGUCCCGCAGCCCUUGUGGGUGGGCCCAUGUCAUUAGCCUCAUUUUAGAGAAGAGUCUUGAUGGGUCGGAGAGCGGUGGCUUACCCACAGUAUGACGCCGUGCCCAUCCAGUCCAGCGUGGUGUUAUGUUCCUGCCCAUCCCCAUCAAUGGUGAGGACCCAGACUGAGUCCAGCACGCCCCCUGGCAUUCCUGGUGGCAGCAGGCAGGGCCCCGCCAUGGACGGCACUGCAGCCGAGCCUCGGCCCGGCGCCGGCUCCCUGCAGCAUGCCCAGCCUCCGCCGCAGCCUCGGAAGAAGCGGCCUGAGGACUUCAAGUUUGGGAAAAUCCUUGGGGAAGGCUCUUUUUCCACGGUUGUCCUGGCUCGAGAACUGGCAACCUCCAGAGAAUAUGCGAUUAAAAUUCUGGAGAAGCGACAUAUCAUAAAAGAGAACAAGGUCCCCUAUGUAACCAGAGAGCGGGAUGUCAUGUCGCGCCUGGAUCACCCCUUCUUUGUUAAGCUUUACUUCACAUUUCAGGACGACGAGAAGCUGUAUUUCGGCCUUAGUUAUGCCAAAAAUGGAGAACUACUUAAAUAUAUUCGCAAAAUCGGUUCAUUCGAUGAGACCUGUACCCGAUUUUACACGGCUGAGAUUGUGUCUGCUUUAGAGUACUUGCACGGCAAGGGCAUCAUUCACAGGGACCUUAAACCGGAAAACAUUUUGUUAAAUGAAGAUAUGCACAUCCAGAUCACAGAUUUUGGAACAGCAAAAGUCUUAUCCCCAGAGAGCAAACAAGCCAGGGCCAACUCAUUCGUGGGAACAGCGCAGUACGUUUCUCCAGAGCUGCUCACGGAGAAGUCCGCCUGUAAGAGUUCAGACCUUUGGGCUCUUGGAUGCAUAAUAUACCAGCUUGUGGCAGGACUCCCACCAUUCCGAGCUGGAAACGAGUAUCUUAUAUUUCAGAAGAUCAUUAAGUUGGAAUAUGACUUUCCAGAAAAAUUCUUCCCUAAGGCAAGAGACCUCGUGGAGAAACUUUUGGUUUUAGAUGCCACAAAGCGGUUAGGCUGUGAGGAAAUGGAAGGAUACGGACCUCUUAAAGCACACCCGUUCUUCGAGUCCGUCACGUGGGAGAACCUGCACCAGCAGACGCCUCCGAAGCUCACCGCUUACCUGCCGGCUAUGUCGGAAGACGACGAGGACUGCUAUGGCAAUUAUGACAAUCUCCUGAGCCAGUUUGGCUGCAUGCAGGUGUCUUCGUCCUCCUCCUCACACUCCCUGUCAGCCUCCGACACGGGCCUGCCCCAGAGGUCAGGCAGCAACAUAGAGCAGUACAUUCACGAUCUGGACUCGAACUCCUUUGAACUGGACUUACAGUUUUCCGAAGAUGAGAAGAGGUUGUUGUUGGAGAAGCAGGCUGGCGGAAACCCUUGGCACCAGUUUGUAGAAAAUAAUUUAAUACUAAAGAUGGGCCCAGUGGAUAAGCGGAAGGGUUUAUUUGCAAGACGACGACAGCUGUUGCUCACAGAAGGACCACAUUUAUAUUAUGUGGAUCCUGUCAACAAAGUUCUGAAAGGUGAAAUUCCUUGGUCACAAGAACUUCGACCAGAGGCCAAGAAUUUUAAAACUUUCUUUGUCCACACGCCUAACAGGACGUAUUAUCUGAUGGACCCCAGCGGGAACGCACACAAGUGGUGCAGGAAGAUCCAGGAGGUUUGGAGGCAGCGAUACCAGAGCCACCCGGACGCCGCUGUGCAGUGACGUGGCCUGCGGCCGGGCUGCCCUUCGCUGCCAGGACACCUGCCCCAGCGCGGCUUGGCCGCCAUCCGGGACGCUUCCAGACCACCUGCCAGCCAUCACAAGGGGAACGCAGAGGCGGAAACCUUGCAGCAUUUUUAUUUAAAAGAAAAGAAGAAAAAAAACACCCAACCACACAAAGAACAAAACCAGUAACAAACACAAAGGAAUUCAGGGUCGCUUUGCUUGCUCUCUGUGCUCCGUGGAGGCCUCCGUGUGCCCUCGUUGCCGUGGGGACCCAGCUCCAUGCACGUCAACCCAGUCCCGCCCAGACUAGUGGACAGACCUGGUGUCACCAGUUUUUCCUAGCAUCAGUCCGAACCAUGCGCCCGCCCUGCCCCAACUGUGUGCUGGUCCUGCUGUGGCCGAGGGGACCGGGUGUGUUUGGCUCUUUAUGCCCCUCCCGCUGUGGUCCUGGAACUCUUCACCAGGGAGGGAGCCCUGCGGGGGCCGCAGCUUUGUGGAGGGAGCCGCCGUGCUUCUGUCACCUGCUCCCUUUCUUGCGUCUCCCUGUGAUGGGCCCUUAGGCCUGGCUGGGCCCAUUACAUAUCCCUGUGGUGGCUCUGGUGGCAGCUUUCUGUGGCCCCUGCUGUGUUGGCAGGCAGGUUUGCGUGGUGAGGAGCGGGAGGGGUUGGAGUGGUGCGGGAGCAGGCUGCCGAGUGGAGGGUGCCAUCGAGGGCUCCGGAUCCCUUAUCCUACUUAGCAGUGUUGGUCUCUGGGGCUGGAAGCCGAGCGCAUGCUGGGAGCGGUACUGUCAGAAGUGAGCCCAGUUAGUACCCCGCUGGCUCACUGCACGAGAGAGUCCUGCCCCGAGCCCUAGGUGGGGCCAGGAGGUGCCUUGGAGAAGCCAGCCAGAGCAGAGAGGGCUGCUGACUUCCGUGUGGAGCAGAGAGGCCUGAGGGCCUCCUAAAAGGUUUAAAUGUCCACGCCUCUCCAGUUGCUGAAGUAGGGUCUGAGAGAACCCUGGCAUCAGCAGACCCAGGGUGCUUCUGUCUCCUGCAGACCACGCCAGGGAGUGCAGACACCACCGUCACACACGCCCCUUUUGUGUUUUGGUUCAAGUUUCUCAGAGCCCCUCAGAGCUUCUACAUCUGUGCAUCAGAAAUCUCACAGCCUUCUCAUGCUGCCGGCUCAUCUGGGCCCAUAGAGUGGGCUUUGCCAGUUGCUGUUGCACAGGAGGCGAGAACAGCACACUUCAACCCCAGCUUGCUGGUCGGCUUUCCUCUAGAGAGAGCCGGUUUUGGGGCCAUUUCCCUUUGAUGCUUUGGUGGCCUUGCCCCGCUCUGCAGCACAGACAGGCCAGAUGCAUUUGUCCUUUGCCUAGCUACUCCCCAGGUAGAGAGUGCUCCUGGUGGCCUGGCAGGUCUGGGCCCUUCUCUCCCUGCCCAGGUUGUCCCUGGAGGGCAGCCCUCACUCCCUUUGGGGGAGAGGCAGACAUUGCUGCCCACAGACCUGCCUCUGACUCAACUGUGUCCACCCUCCCUGGUCCCUACCCCCAAGUCACAGGUGACUCAGCAGUGACCCUGUGUGCCAGGCCAGAUCCAAACUGAGAGGGAAGGUGUCGUUUUUACACUGCUAAUGACGAGAGUGGCUCUUUUUAGCUAGGCGAGUACAGACGGGGCCUGGGAGGGGGCAGAGAUGUUCCCCAGGCCCUGCCUGUGGUUCCUGCCUGGGCCUUGGCUGCUGCUGUGUGAGAGCUGCAUGUGAGCCUGUGACCGUGAGCUGGGGUGAGCUGGGCCGCACCUACCCUGGGGCCCCAGGGAGCAGGACGCUCCGGGGCCCAGCACGUUGCCCUGGGCCUGUGGCCGGAGUCGGAGUCCUCUCUCCUCCUCCUGGCUUUUGGAAAGGCUUGGCUGUGUUGGGGAGUCUCUCUUAGCCCUUUCAGGAAUUUCUGUUCAGGCUUCCUCCUCCUCAUCAGCUAUUUUACCCAUCUCAGAACGUCCUGUGUCUCCAUGUAGGAGAGUGGCUCUCUCAGAUCUCUCAGGGCGUCUGGUUAUAGGGAAACAAGUGGAGCAGGGACGUGGCUUUAAUUGGAGCACUCGGCUGGGCUGCUUGGGGAGACUCUUCCGUGCGUUCUUCCUCUGGAUAGAACCACCACCUCCUGGGCGUCACUGACAAGCUCCAUCUUAACCUCCAAAGCCACAGAACUAGGGGCUCAGAGCCAGAGCUGGCAGCCGCCAGCCAAAAUGAUGCCAUUGCCUGAGCUGACAGCCAAGCCCUUCUGUGGGUCACCUUUCUCCUCACCCAGCCCCUUGCUCUUCCCUUUUGAAAGGCCCGUGUGUUUUCUUUCCUUACCCUGUGCUUGCUCAUGUCUACUCCGGUUUUCUCUACCACAUCCUUAGAGCCAUCACCUGGCACGCAGGCGCCUUACAUUCUACGGUAGAACGUGGGGUACUGUGUGUGCACAUAGACACACUUACGUGGAAUUACAGUUGUGGGUUUAUCCAAGAUGAGGAAGAUUUCACCUGCUGUUUAAUAGACUUGGGGCCAUGUGCCUCCCCACACAUGGGCAAGGACAGGUGGAAUGUCGGGACCACACUGUGCGGCUUCUCGGCACAAAGCGGAGGGAGGCUGUGGUCGCUGCCGGCCUAGGUGUCCCAGGUGCCCCGCCUUUCUCUGGGACACAGUUGGGGGCUGGCUUCUGAGGGAUUCCUUUCUCCCCUCUUUGUGUGGCCCCAGCCAGGGCGGUGGGCAGUCCUGGUGUAGAGCACAAGCCUCUCCACCCUAGAGAAAUGCCUCUGUACCACGGCUACCAUGUGGAACCUUAACUUGCAGAAGGCUUGUUAACAAUUGUUUUGAGAGAGAUGGCUGGUCAUGCCACAGCUGCUGGGGACUCCGCCUACUCCAGCCCUCUUGGGACACACUGUGGGAUUUGUGGCCCUUCCCCAGAGGAAUUGUGGAGACUGUCCCAUGGAACAAACCCUCAGGCACCAGCACAGGGCUCUGGGUGACUCAGUAAAACUAACGUUUGUCUCUGACAAGAUCAGCUGUAGGCUCACCGGCCAGAGAAGACCACUGUGAGCAUUUUGCCGUAUAUCCUGCCCUGCCAUUUGUUCACUUUUUAAACUAAAAUAGGAACAUCCGACACACACCGUUUGCAUCGUCUUCUCCCUUGAUAUUUUAAGCAUUUUCCCAUGUCAUGAGUUUCUCAGAAACAUGUUUUUAACAAUUGUACUAUUUAGUCAUUGUCCAUUUACUAUAAUUUAUCUGACCAUUUCCCUACUGUAAAAUACUUAAGACGGUUUCUGAUUUUUCCACUAUUUAAAUAAUGCUGUGAUGAAUAUCUUUAAAAUCUUCUGAUUUCUUACUUUUUUCCCCCUUAGAUGCCUGGAAGUGGUAUUUUGAGGUGAAAGAGUUUGUUCAUUUUGAAGAUAUUUCUGUCUCUCUCUCGACCUGAUGUGUAGACGCUCACUUCCAGUAGCAGAACCACCUUAGUUGUGUCUUACAGAUUCUGAACAAAUCGGUUUCUGAUAAGCCAUGUGUUCCAAAGAAUGUCUGAAUAAGACCGCUCUUUAUUUAAAUGCUAAGAGGAUGUCACUACUGCAAUCCAUCUGUGGCCGAUUUUUUCCAAGAGCCAAUUUCCUUGUUUUGGUUGCAAGAACCUGGCUCUGCCUGCAUGUCAGCUCUCUGCCCUCCCUGCUGCCGUGGCUUUCAAGCGCUUGGCAGAAUCUUGUACUUCGUGUCCACAAUGGUACUGAAUUUGCAUCUGCACAGUCAGCAGAGAUAACAAGUGUUGAACUGACCUUGCCACAUGCUUAGUGAGUGAUUUGUAAUUAAGUUUAUAGACUCAGAAGGUAUAUUAGGACAUUUGGAAUCAGUAGCAGAGCAAAGCCUCUUUGAAAAAAACCACGUAGCUGAUUGGGUUUUACAAGAGUGCAUUUGUCUCCCCCUUCCACCCGUGGGGCCCCACCUUCAGGUCUUAGUGGUUCACAAGAGCCCAGCAGCCAGGCUGGCUUUUUCAUUGUAGGGCGUGGUUGUCCCAGCUGGUGUAGAUUUCAGGCCGCCCCCCCCAACUCCCUGCCCACAGUGUUGCAGAUUGCCUGGCUGGCAGCAAGUCCAGACCACCCAAAUUUGGUUGGAUUCUUCAUUUCUCCACUGUAGUUGGGGUCCAUUGAUUGUGCAGGGGAACGUGCAGGAGGUUUUUCUAGGCACCGUGUUCAGUGCUGCUUCACUCUACCAGAGAUUAUGGCCAAAUUGCACGGAAUUUGGUUUCUUGCCCUCUGAAGCCUGAGGGCCCCCCCUUGCCUGGCUGGUUGACAGACCCGGGGUGGUCACUGCUGAGACUUCAGAGAUCGCAGCUGCUGUGAGAAUACGGUGAAGGUACUUUGUUCUGGAAGAUGUUGUCAUACACUUUUCCCCAGUUAUUUUCAAACUUGACAUGAGCCUAUGUUGACUCACUGGGUGGGGGUCCCUUCUUACGCAGCACACGUGGCAAGUGCCUGAAUCGGGGCUGGAGGCACUUCAGAGCCUCUGAGGGGCCACCACUUCUGGCCCAAAAUUGCAGGGUUGUAGAUGAGGCUGCCUGUGGAGAACUGGUGUGAGGAGGAAGCUGUUUCCAACAAAGAGCACUUUCAUCUGUUGAGAUGGCUGUGGUGAGCAACUGAACGAGCCUACGUGUGUACCUGAAUUUUCCCCGUAACUCAUUUCUUCCAUAUGAAGAAACACCAAACUAUGUACAGAGAACUUUUUACAAAAGGCAGACCUUUUUUAAGCUGUGUAACCCACAUAGCCUAACCACCUGGCAGAAUGACUACGAAUAGGGGUCAUUGUGCUGGUAAAAGCCUCUAUUACGACUGUAAGUAAGUUGGAUGUUGGCAAAAUUAAAUUGUUACAGUAUUUAGAGCUGCUGUAGCUGUUCCUUCACAACAUAAAAUAGGAUAAAUGACUAGUACGUCUUUCAGGUGGGUGGCAAGCAGAACAUGCGUAAUAUUCUCUACCUGGUCUGUAGCUGUAACUGUGAUGUACAGACAAAGCAAAAAUUAAAAGAACUUAUGAAAACAAAUGCAAUGAUACUAGGAUAUACACUUUUGUAUUUUUAUUCUUAUAUAAGGUUAUUUGCUGGCUAUUGUUGGCCUCUAGUUCAGUCUGUGUUAUUUAAAUUCUAAUAUAUGAAUUAUUUGAAUUGAAUUCAUGUUCGGGGCCACGUUGUUGUAUGUAUUGAUGUACAGCCUUGAAUGUGAAUAAUUAUUGUAAACUAUAUUUUACAACUUUUUUUCUGGCUUUAUUAUAUAAAUUUUCUAUUGGGUCAGUGAUUUAAUCAUAUAAUUUAAUGAAUCUGUUUAUCCUUUUUUUUUUUCCAAAUACUUGUGCUUUAGGUGUAGUUACCAGAUGAUGAAUUUUCCUCGUAUGGUCAGUAGUCUUGUAAUAAAAAGCAUGUAGAGUGUA